UUGAACCGAGGAGGCGGAGGUUGCAGUGAGUUGAGAGUCCGCGCACCGUUGGCACCGCGAUGAGGGCGGGAAGCACAGCGCGGGGCCCCCGGGAGCAAGAACGCCGCGGGCACCCAGCCCUCGUGGGAGGCGGCGGUCGGGGCACGCCCCGGGCCGAACCAGGCUCUGCACUCCCGCGGGUGCCCGGACCUGAAGGGUCGUCCGCUGGCUCCAGGAUUCUGCAUCCCCGACCCGCUCCGGGUGCGCCGAGGCUGCUGGGACUUCGCUGCGGGAGCGCGCCCGGGGCCCCGGGGCCUGCACGGAAGGCGGCUGCGGGGAGGGUGGCCGGGCAGAGGCUUCGGUCCCGGGCGCCCCCUCCCCGGCCGGACCCCCCUCCCCGGCCGGACCCCGAGUCUGCAGUCUCCGCAGGAGUCCUGAGAGAAGUGAUUGCUGGUGAUGAUUCGCACCUAGGAAUCACAGUGAUUCGCACCUCGGUAACGCCGCAGCUUCGUCUCUGUGACUCUGGUGGCCUUUUAUUCCUGCUUGUUACCUCCUGGUCAUGA